GCUGGCCCCUGGGGACGCCGAGGGCGGCUGCGACGCGCCGAGAGGCCGCGGCUCUCCCACCUGUCACCCUGGCCCUUCUCUGCUUGGAUGGUGUCUUCCUCUCCUCAGCCGAGAAUGACUUCGUCCACCGGAUCCAGGAGGAACUGGACCGCUUUCUGCUGCAGAAGCAGCUGUCAAAGGUUCUUCUUUUCCCCCCACUCUCCAGUCGCCUCCGGUACCUGAUCCAUAGAACAGCAGAGAAUUUUGAUCUCUUGAGCAGCUUCUCCGUUGGGGAGGGCUGGAAGAGGAGGACGGUCAUCUGUCACCAGGACAUCAGGGUACCCAGUUCGGAUGGCCUCUCUGGCCCCUGCCGCGCUCCUGCCUCCUGCCCCAGCAGGUACCACGGUCCUCGGCCCAUCUCCAACCAAGGAGCAGCUGCGGUUCCCCGAGGUGCCCGGGCUGGCCGGUGGUAUCGUGGACGCAAGCCUGACCAGCCUUUGUAUGUGCCCCGGGUGCUGCGCAGGCAGGAAGAAUGGGGGCUGACCUCUACCUCGGUGCUCAAGAGAGAGGCCCCAGCUGGCAGGGACCCAGAAGAGCCUGGAGAUGUUGGUGCUGGAGACCCCAACUCUGAUCAGGGACUCCCUGUGCUGAUGACUCAGGGAACAGAGGACCUAAAGGGCCCAGGACAAAGGUGUGAGAAUGAGCCACUGCUGGACCCUGUUGGCCCUGAGCCUCUGGGGCCUGAGAGUCAGUCAGGGAAGGGAGACAUGGUGGAGAUGGCCACACGGUUUGGGUCCACCCUGCAGCUAGACCUGGAAAAGGGGAAGGAGAGUCUGUUGGAGAAGAGGCUGGUGGCAGAGGAGGAAGAGGACGAAGAGGAGGUGGAAGAGGAUGGCCCCAGCAGCUGCUCGGAGGACGAUUACAGUGAGCUGCUGCAGGAGAUCACAGACAACCUGACGAAGAAGGAGAUUCAGAUAGAGAAGAUCCAUUUGGACACAUCCUCCUUCGUGGAGGAGCUGCCUGGAGAGAAGGACCUUGCCCACGUGGUAGAGAUCUAUGACUUUGAACCAGCGCUCAAGACGGAGGACCUGCUGGCAACGUUUUCUGAGUUCCAAGAGAAGGGGUUCAGGAUUCAGUGGGUGGAUGAUACUCACGCACUCGGCAUCUUUCCCUGCCUGGCCUCAGCUGCGGAAGCCCUGACCCGGGAGUUCUCGGUGCUCAAGAUCCGGCCCCUCACACAGGGAACCAAGCAGUCAAAGCUCAAAGCCUUGCAGAGGCCAAAACUCCUGCGUCUGGUGAAGGAGAGGCCACAGACAAAUGCGACUGUGGCCCGGCGGCUGGUGGCCCGGGCCCUGGGACUCCAACACAAAAAGAAAGAGCGGCCUGCUGUCCGGGGUCCGCUGCCGCCCUGAGGCCUGGAGACCCAACUGGCCUGGAUCUGCGUCCCGACGUAGCUGGCGCCCCCAACACCAUAAGCCUUCACAGACGCCAGAGCAGCCCCGCACCACCCUCGAGCUUCACCAUGGGGUGUGGUGGGCUUUAGUUUAGUCCCAGAAAUGGAGAAAAAAUAAAAACUCACGUUGUUCUAAUGUGA